GCUCCGACGCCGUCGCUGGGACCAAGAUGGACCUCCCGGCGCUGCUCCCCGCCCCGACUGCGCGCGGAGGGCAACAUGGCGGCGGCCCCGGCCCGCUCCGCCGAGCCCCAGCGCCGCUCGGCGCGAGCCCCGCGCGCCGCCGCCUGCUACUGGUGCGGGGCCCUGAAGAUGGCGGGCCCGGGGCGCGGCCCGGGGAGGCCUCCGGGCCAAGCCCGCCGCCCGCCGAGGACGACAGCGACGGCGACUCUUUCUUGGUGCUGCUGGAAGUGCCGCACGGCGGCGCUGCCGCCGAGGCUGCCGGAUCACAGGAGGCCGAGCCUGGCUCCCGUGUCAACCUGGCGAGCCGCCCCGAGCAGGGCCCCAGCGGCCCGGCCGCCCCCCCCGGCCCUGGCGUAGCCCCGGCGGGCGCCGUCACCAUCAGCAGCCAGGACCUGCUGGUGCGUCUCGACCGCGGCGUCCUCGCGCUGUCUGCGCCGCCCGGCCCCGCAACCGCGGGCGCCGCCGCUCCCCGCCGCGCGCCCCAGGCCUCCGGCCCCAGCACGCCCGGCUACCGCUGCCCCGAGCCGCAGUGCGCGCUGGCCUUCGCCAAGAAGCACCAGCUCAAGGUGCACCUGCUCACGCACGGCGGCGGUCAGGGCCGGCGGCCCUUCAAGUGCCCACUGGAGGGCUGUGGUUGGGCCUUCACAACGUCCUACAAGCUCAAGCGGCACCUGCAGUCGCACGACAAGCUGCGGCCCUUCGGCUGUCCAGUGGGCGGCUGUGGCAAGAAGUUCACUACGGUCUAUAACCUCAAGGCGCACAUGAAGGGCCACGAGCAGGAGAGCCUGUUCAAGUGCGAGGUGUGCGCCGAGCGCUUCCCCACGCACGCCAAGCUCAGCUCCCACCAGCGCAGCCACUUCGAGCCCGAGCGCCCUUACAAGUGUGACUUUCCCGGCUGUGAGAAGACAUUUAUCACAGUGAGUGCCCUGUUUUCCCAUAACCGAGCCCACUUCAGGGAACAAGAGCUCUUUUCCUGCUCCUUUCCUGGGUGCAGCAAGCAGUAUGAUAAAGCCUGUCGGCUGAAAAUUCACCUGCGGAGCCAUACAGGUGAAAGACCAUUUAUUUGUGACUCUGACAGCUGUGGCUGGACCUUCACCAGCAUGUCCAAACUUCUAAGGCACAGAAGGAAACAUGACGAUGACCGGAGGUUUACCUGCCCUGUCGAGGGCUGUGGGAAAUCAUUCACCAGAGCAGAGCAUCUGAAAGGCCACAGCAUAACCCACCUAGGCACAAAGCCGUUCGAGUGUCCUGUGGAAGGAUGUUGCGCGAGGUUCUCCGCUCGUAGCAGUCUGUACAUUCACUCUAAGAAACACGUGCAGGAUGUGGGUGCUCCGAAAAGCCGUUGCCCAGUUUCUACCUGCAACAGACUCUUCACCUCCAAGCACAGCAUGAAGGCGCACAUGGUCAGACAGCACAGCCGGCGCCAAGAUCUCUUACCUCAGCUAGAAGCUCCGAGUUCUCUUACUCCCAGCAGUGAACUCAGCAGCCCAGGCCAAAGUGAGCUCACUAACAUGGAUCUUGCUGCACUCUUCUCUGACACACCUGCCAAUGCUAGUGGUUCUGCAGGUGGGUCGGAUGAGGCUCUGAACUCCGGAAUCCUGACUAUUGACGUCACUUCUGUGAGCUCCUCUCUGGGAGGGAACCUCCCUGCUAAUAAUAGCUCCCUAGGGCCGAUGGAACCCCUGGUCCUGGUGGCCCACAGUGAUAUUCCCCCAAGCCUGGACAGCCCUCUGGUUCUCGGGACAGCAGCCACGGUUCUGCAGCAGGGCAGCUUCAGUGUGGAUGACGUGCAGACUGUGAGUGCAGGAGCAUUAGGCUGUCUGGUGGCUCUGCCCAUGAAGAACUUGAGUGACGACCCACUGGCUUUGACCUCCAAUAGUAACUUAGCAGCACAUAUCACCACACCGACCUCUUCGAGCACCCCCCGAGAAAAUGCCAGUGUCCCGGAACUGCUGGCUCCAAUCAAGGUGGAGCCGGACUCGCCUUCUCGCCCAGGAGCAGUUGGGCAGCAGGAAGGAAGCCAUGGGCUGCCCCAGUCCACGUUGCCCAGUCCAGCAGAGCAGCACGGUGCCCAGGACACAGAGCUCAGUGCAGGCACUGGCAACUUCUAUUUGGUAUGAAGCACUCUAUUCAGUCACCACCAUAUAGGUCACUUCUCUCAUACUCGGUCUUGAGGAUAUUCUGGAUUAAUCCUUUCUAUGCAGACGUUUCUGGUUUACAAAAGGACGCAGCCCUGGACUACAAGUCUGGAACUGACAAGUUCUUAUGACCUUGACAAAUCACCUUAACCCAUCUGAGCCUUAAAUUCUCAUUUAUUUCCUGCAUAAGGAGAUUUGGCUAAAUGCUUUCUGAGGUCCUUUGGAGUCCUGUGGCUCCAUGGUAAUGUGCUCCUUUCCUUGAAGAUUGGGGGUUUUGUAAUGUUGAGAUACUUUGCCUCUAUGCUUGUCAGCUCAUGACCAGUCCUAGAAGAGGAGUCGAGACAUAAGCCACCUUCAGAGGUUCAAUGGAAACUUUAAAACCAUACCAAACUCUUUUUUAAAAUUAGAAUUAACAAGAAAAAAAAAAAGGGUGGGGUUUAUGAGCCUUAGUUCUUGGAGGAUUAUAAGAGUACUUCCCCAGUUUUGAGGCUGGACAGUUAAUAUACUUUAUAUCAAUUAUACAUUUAAUAUAAUUUAAUUUAAAAUAAUUUAAAGAUUCUUAGGAGAUAGUCUGACUUUCCUGACCUAGAUGGGAAUGAUCAGAUAGGGAUUUUUUUUGUGGCACAGGCUAAAUUUGAUGGUGACAUUUAUAUUGUUGAGAAUGUUACAUCUUAUUUUACCACAACUUUUAAAAAAUGUUACAUCUUUUGCAGUAGGAUCAGUUGUGAGGCACAUAGUAGCUGAGGCUCCAUGGAGCCACCUUUCAUUUCUUUCAGUCAGAGAGGAGGACAGUCUCUGUCUCUGCAUUUCUGGUGUCUUGCUUGUCGGUGGCAGAGCCAUGCUUGCCGGCAUUUGCUUAGGCGGCCAUAGUAGUUGCUAAGUGUACAGGUGACUGGGCAGGGAUGGGAGGUGGCCACAGGUCAGAGACAAGUGCUCAGUCAGUCCCUGGUGCCAGGACUGUGUGCCUCGGUGCCUUGGGAAAUGGAAGCUCCCUGGUGCAGCUGCAGCUGUGGGUGGAGGUAGAGAAGCCAGCAAGACCUUGGUCUUAACCCCGUGUUCAUUUUCUUGCUAGCUGUGUGACGUUGGGCUACCUCGCUUCUCUGAGUACAAAUGGUGUGUGGUGAAUGGGUCCCAGGUAUGCUACGAGCUUUGAGGGCUGCUCUUUUUCUCUUCAUAGCGAUAAGUGUUAAACUGUCUUUCUUAGGAAACGUUCACAGACUUGCAACAGCUGAUGUCCUCUGAGUACUGUCUGACUCCCUCAGGCAAGUUCCUGAAUUCAGUACCAUCAUUAUUAUUUUUGUGUAAGACUUUGACAAAGUAUAGCCCCUGCCACCAGAGCAGCCUGUACAGUGGGUCUCUAAGGUGGGACCUGCCCCGGGCCUGCCAUGCACGUGUGUGAAACAGCGUGAAAAGUGUCGCGGUAAGGUGACCCUGGGUUACCCAGGCAAGGCUCGGUGUUUGUUUCAGAAAGCAGAGAAGUAUGUAAUUGAUUUUAAAAGUUUCUGUUUAAAAUAUUUGGCUAUGUUUUAGACUAUGAAGGAAUGAACUUUGCUUCUCUGGAUAAGAAAGUCACAUACAUUGUUCCAGCUCCAAGUUUGUUCGGCCCUCGCCACAAGUGGAUGUAGCGUUUGGCCCUUUGUGUGCCUUGCUGGUGACUCUGGUUUUGGGAGCUCGGAUAUGUCCCAGAAGCAGGCUUAUGGCACUUCUGUAGCUCCCUUGCUACCCUUCCUUUGUGUCUAGAUAAGUGACUGACAUGCUUUUCUUUGGUCUCAGGAAAGUGGGGGCUCAGCAAGAACUGAUUACCGAGCCAUUCAACUAGCCAAGGAAAAAAAGCAGAGAGGAGCGGGGAGCAAUGCAGGUGAGGCCGUGUGUGCUGCAGCCGGACGAGCAAGGGCCUGAGGGUUCUCUGUCACUGUUACUGGCAGAAGAAACACAGCAGGUGUUUCUGUGCUCUUGGUUUUACUUUUCUGUUCAGAAUACCCUUUUAUCAACUCCUUAGUUUUAUUUGAACUUAAGGGAAAAAAUUAGUAACAAAAUUCCCAGCAUCAGUAUGAACAUAUUUUAUUUGCCUAAACAAGCUUUGUGAAAGUUAAGCGUUCAAACACCAGUGUCAGUUACCUGGAAGGCUACUAAGGUAAAUAAGCAAAGCAGGCCAGUUGUCAGGAAAGCAGAGAUUGUGCCUGGUGCUGAAUGGCCUUGGGGCCUGAUCUUGGCAUGGCAGAGACCUGGGGACUGCCACUGUCCCCAGGUACGUGUACAUGGAGCCAAACUGUGUGUCCUGUGGCAUUGUCAGAGUUAUGUUGAAAUCUUAUUUGAAAAUGUUAGCAACUUACUUGCAUUUUUAAAGACCAAACAAGAGCUGGUAACCUAUGGCCUCAAGCAUCUGUCCUUCCUAAAAAUGGAAUAGUGGGAUGUAGUGCUUAAUGGAAACUGCUAAAUCUUUUUCUAAAAACUAACAGUGGAUUUUUAAAAUAUAUUGUUUUUUGUGUAUUUCAUUUGUCCUUUGUAUUUAUCUAAAAGGGUUGAUAUGAUUUUAUAUCUUGCUCUCUAUUCCUAAUAGUAUUAUGACUUCUUAUUUAAAAUAAAUAACAAUUGCCGGUUUUCUGUUAA